GCUUCCUGGGCGCCGUGGGCGCGGACUGCGCGGGCUGCGCGGGUGCCGAGGAGCGCGAGGCGCGGGGAAGGCGCACCUGGGGUGGCCCUGGCGUGCGGGCGGCGACAUGGAGGACGGCGUGCUCAAGGAGGGCUUCCUGGUCAAGAGGUUUCUUUCAAGAUUUAAAACCAGAGAAAUGGCCAAAUAGGAACUAGAAGGGCCACAUUGUCCACAACUGGAAGGCGCGAUGGUUCAUCCUUCGGCAGAACACGCUGGUGUACUACAAGCUUGAGGGGGGUCGGAGAGUGACCCCUCCCAAGGGCCGGAUCCUCCUGGAUGGCUGCACCAUCACCUGCCCCUGCCUGGAGUAUGAAAACCGACCGCUCCUCAUUAAGCUGAAGACUCAAACAUCCACGGAGUACUUCCUGGAGGCCUGUUCUCGAGAGGAGCGGGAUGCCUGGGCCUUUGAGAUCACCGGGGCUAUUCAUGCAGGGCAGCCGGGGAAGGUCCAGCAGCUGCACAGCCUGAGAAACUCCUUCAAGCUGCCCCCGCACAUCAGCCUGCAUCGCAUUGUGGACAAGAUGCACGAUAGCAACACCGGAAUCCGUUCAAGCCCCAACAUGGAGCAGGGAAGCACCUAUAAAAAGACCUUCCUCGGCUCCUCCCUGGUGGACUGGCUCAUCUCCAACAGCUUCACGGCCAGCCGUCUGGAGGCGGUGACCCUGGCCUCCAUGCUCAUGGAGGAGAACUUCCUCAGGCCUGUGGGUGUCCGAAGCAUGGGAGCCAUUCGCUCUGGGGAUCUGGCCGAGCAGUUCCUGGAUGACUCCACAGCCCUGUACACUUUUGCUGAGAGCUACAAAAAGAAGAUAAGCCCCAAGGAAGAAAUUAGCCUGAGCACUGUGGAGUUAAGUGGCACGGUGGUGAAACAAGGCUACCUGGCCAAGCAGGGACACAAGAGGAAAAACUGGAAGGUGCGUCGCUUUGUUCUAAGGAAGGAUCCAGCUUUCCUGCAUUACUAUGACCCUUCCAAAGAAGAGAACAGGCCAGUGGGUGGGUUUUCUCUUCGUGGUUCACUCGUGUCUGCUCUGGAAGAUAAUGGCGUUCCCACUGGGGUUAAAGGGAAUGUCCAGGGAAACCUCUUCAAAGUGAUUACUAAGGAUGACACACACUAUUACAUUCAGGCCAGCAGCAAGGCUGAGCGAGCCGAGUGGAUUGAAGCUAUCAAAAAGCUAACAUGACAAGGACCUGAGGGAACCAGGAUUCCUCCCUCCUACCAGAUGACACAGACAAGAGUUCCUGGAGAAUGGGAGUGUUAAGACUUUUGACUUCUUUGUAAGUUUUGUACUGCUUUGGAGAGUGAAUGCUGCCAAGAGUUCCUCAGAUUACAAACAGCAGUGGUGCCAUUUCCUUCCCCAUCUUCAUGUUACAAACCUGGAAAGGCUAGAACAGCCAUUAGGCGUCAGCAUCUUGACUUUUCCCCAGCAUCACAAACAGCCAUUUCCUCGGGCACCAAAGUAGGUUCCCUUUGUUGGAACAAUUACACUGGCCAUGCCAUAAUGUUGAAUAAAACUCUCUUCUUAUGA